AGAGGGGGCGUCAGGCCGCGGGAGAGGAGGCCAUGGGCGCGCGCGGGGCGCUGCUGCUGGCGCUGCUGCUGGCUCGGGCUGGACUCAGGAAGCCGGAGUCGCAGGAGGCGGCGCCGUUAUCAGGACCAUGCGGCCGACGGGUCAUCACGUCGCGCAUCGUGGGUGGAGAGGACGCCGAACUCGGGCGUUGGCCGUGGCAGGGGAGCCUGCGCCUGUGGGAUUCCCACGUAUGCGGAGUGAGCCUGCUCAGCCACCGCUGGGCACUCACGGCGGCGCACUGCUUUGAAACCUAUAGUGACCUUAGUGAUCCCUCCGGGUGGAUGGUCCAGUUUGGCCAGCUGACUUCCAUGCCAUCCUUCUGGAGCCUGCAGGCCUACUACACCCGUUACUUCGUAUCGAAUAUCUAUCUGAGCCCUCGCUACCUGGGGAAUUCACCCUAUGACAUUGCCUUGGUGAAGCUGUCUGCACCUGUCACCUACACUAAACACAUCCAGCCCAUCUGUCUCCAGGCCUCCACAUUUGAGUUUGAGAACCGGACAGACUGCUGGGUGACUGGCUGGGGGUACAUCAAAGAGGAUGAGGGACAAGGUGCUGGCUGGCACUCUGAGGCAGGAAUUGGACAGGUGUGGGCUCCUGUCAGGCUCUGAAACUUCCCCAGUGCCUUGCUGGGGGUCAGCGGGGCAAUAUCCCCCUGACUCUCCUUAUCUGGGAGUAGGUCCUGAUGACUGCCGCCUCCCAGGGGUGCUGGGGGUCCCUAAGAGUGCUGCAACAAGCUUGUGUCCAGGCCUGGAAAGCGCCCAGCUGCUACUGAGGCCAGGGCUGCAGCCAGGCUGCCCCUCCCCCAGGUCUGGCUUUGGAUGCUCAUCUGAACACCGUCUCAGCUGCCUUCGCCCCUCCCUCGGCUCCUUUUGGCUGAGGAAUCUCUCCAUGGCUGCAGGCAGGGCCAUUGUUGCCAUUCUACAGAUAGGGAAAGUGCGGCUGGGGGAGCUCUGACAGCCUGUCCCUCCCCGGGGCCUUCUGUGAUGCUGCUGAGGGCCUCUGUUGUGCUGGGGUCUGGGUUGGAGCUGGGGGUAAUGGAGAUGAACCUGCCAGGCACAGUGGGUGCCCCAGGGCCCCCACCCCCGCAGCCUAUGCCAUCCCUCCAUAGAGGGGCCUCAGGUUGCUGUCUCUCUCCUUCCCACUAUCGUCCGCACAGCACUGCCAUCUCCCCACACCCUCCAGGAAGUUCAGGUCGCCAUCAUAAACAACUCUAUGUGCAACCACCUCUUCCUCAAGUACAGUUUCCGCAAGGACAUCUUUGGAGACAUGGUUUGUGCUGGCAAUGCCCAAGGCGGGAAGGAUGCCUGCUUCGUGAGUGUCCUUGCCACCACUCCCAGCCCAGGAAAGCAUCCUGUGUCCCUGUGCCUUAUUUGACCCUCAUGCCAACCCCGGGAGGUGGAGACUGUUGCCCCACUCUGCAGAUGCAGAAACGGAGGCUUGGCUGCUGCCAGGGGGAGGAGGAGGAUGUGCACCCAGUCUACCCAGCCCCAUAGCCCUUCCCACUCUCAGCCCCUCCCCUGCCCCACUCACUCUGCCCCAGGCUGACCUCAGCCCCGCUGCUCCCCAGGGUGACUCAGGUGGACCCUUGGCCUGUAACAAGAAUGGACUGUGGUAUCAGAUUGGAGUCGUGAGCUGGGGAGUGGGCUGUGGUCGGCCCAAUCGGCCCGGUGUCUACACCAAUAUCAGCCACCACUUUGAGUGGAUCCAGAAGCUGAUGGCCCAGAGUGGCAUGUCCCAGCCAGACCCCUCCUGGCCGCUACUCUUUUUCCCUCUUCUCUGGGCUCUCCCACUCCUGGGGCCGGUCUGAGCCUACCUGAGCCCAUGCAGCCUGGGGCCACUGCCAAGUCAGGCCCUGGUUCUCUUCUGUCUUGUUUGGUAAUAAACACAUUCCAGUUGAUGCCUUGCAGGGCAUUCUUCAAAA